AUCGGCAGAACCGGAGGCCAACCUUCGCGAUCCCUUGCUGCGGGCCCGGAGAUCAAACGUGGCCCGCCCCCGGCAGGGCACAGCGCGCUGGGCAACCGCGAUCCGGCGCCGGACUGGAGGGGUCGAUGCGCGGCGCGCUGGGGCGCACAGGGGACGGAGCCCGGGUCUUGCUCCCCAUUGGCCGCCACCUCGGCGGGAGGGGCCGCCUCCGGCUCGUGGCACCUGGCGUCUCCCCUCCGCGGGGAAAUCGGCGGCUACCCGGCACCGGCGCCUGGAGGUAAAGGUACCCGGGGGUGGGGAAGGCCCCUGGCCGCGGCAGAGCUCCCUGCCACCGGCCCUGUCCUGCUUGCCGCCCCAGCGCCUGCGACGCUUGGAUGCCCCCAGCUCCGGCCGCGCCAACCAGAAACUUUGCCCCUCGAAGUCCCCCGCCUGCCUGACCGCACCGUGAGGCGCCAAGUCGGCCGCGCGCCCCCCGGGGCCCCGGAACCCCGCGAGUCAUUGCCUGGCCGCCCCGUACCCCGCGCCCGCGGCGCCCGGUAGCCAGGAUGCGCUACGCGGACCCCUCGGCCAACCGGGAUUUGUUGGGGAGCCGAACUUUGCUCUUCAUCUUCAUCUGCGCCUUUGCCUUGGUGACCUUGCUGCAACAGAUCCUGUAUGGCAGGAACUACAUUAAGAGAGGCCUCCAGUUUGGUUGGCAGAGUGGUGACCAGCUGACCAAUUGGACGGGGCUCUUUAAUGUCACGGAUGAUCCAGCAGUGCAGAGCGGCAGUGACUCCAGCUCCAGGUACUUUGAAUUUUAUGAGGGGCCUUUUGAAUAUAACUCCACAAGAUGCCUGGAGCUGAGGCACGAAAUAUUGGAAGUGAAGGUGCUGUCCAUGGUGAAGCAGUCAGAGCUGUUCGACAGGUGGAAGAGCCUCCAGAUGUGCAAAUGGGCGAUGAACAUCUCUGAGGCCAACCAGUUCAAGUCUACUCUGUCCAGGUGCUGCAACGCCCCUGCCUUUCUCUUCACCACCCAGAAGAACACUCCCCUGGGGACAAAGCUCAAGUAUGAGGUGGACACCAGUGGCAUCUACCACAUCAACCAGGAGAUCUUCCGCAUGUUUCCCAAGGACAUGCCCUACUACCGGUCCCAGUUUAAGAAGUGUGCUGUAGUGGGCAACGGAGGCAUCUUGAAGAACAGCCGCUGCGGGAGGGAGAUCAACAGCGCCGACUUCGUCUUCCGGUGCAACCUGCCCCCCAUCUCAGAGAAGUACACCAUGGAUGUGGGGGUGAAGACGGAUGUGGUCACUGUGAACCCCAGCAUCAUCACAGAGAGGUUCCACAAGCUGGAGAAGUGGCGGCGGCCGUUCUAUCGCGUGCUGCAGGUGUACGAGAACGCGUCGGUGCUGCUGCCUGCCUUCUACAACACGCGCAACACCGACGUGUCCAUCCGCGUCAAGUACGUGCUGGACGACUUCGAAUCGCCGCAAGCUGUCUACUACUUCCAUCCGCAGUACCUGGUCAACGUGUCGCGCUACUGGCUCAGCCUGGGGGUGCGCGCCAAGCGCAUCAGCACCGGCCUCAUUCUGGUCACUGCGGCGCUGGAGCUCUGUGAGGAGGUGCACCUCUUUGGCUUCUGGGCCUUCCCCAUGAACCCCUCGGGCCUCUACAUCACUCACCACUACUAUGACAACGUCAAGCCGCGUCCCGGCUUCCACGCCAUGCCCUCUGAGAUCUUCAACUUCCUGCACUUGCACAGCCGAGGCAUCCUCCGCGUGCACACGGGCACCUGCAGCUGCUGCUGAUGGCUGCCAGCCAGGCUGCCCGGCAAGCGGCGCCCCCUCUCCUGCUGUCCCUCCUGGUGGAACUGGGAGCCCCGAACCGGGCAGCGUGGGGUCCUGGCGUUCAGGCUGUCUCUCCCUCCAUUGUUCAGCUCUGUACUUGGAUCCUGGGGUAGGGAGGCAGGGUUAGGAACCGGGGCAGAGUCAGCUCUGUGCUGAGCCUCCUGGCCUGGCCCCCACCGGUGCAUCCGCCCAGUGCGUCCACCUGCCCUGGCUAGCAUGCUGCUGGGCCACACCCCAAGAUCAGGGGCCCUGGGGACGGCAAGUGAAUAAAGCACAUUUCCACCCAAUUUUGUCAUCCGAGAGAGAGCACAAACUGCAGGCCCUUGUUGCAGCUGAAGGAAGACCCUACAGAGAAUGGAAUUGAGAGUGGAGACAGGACACUUCACAGGACACUUGAGCACAGUCAAGAUUUUAUUCACACUUUUGGUUCCUGUGUUUUAUAUCGAAGACUUAGCUAUGAAUUGCUAUCUAAAUCUCAGAGCUUAGAAGCCAACCCAGUGACUAGACCUUCCAGUGAAGAAAGUGAUCUCAAGAGGUCCAGGGACUUAACAGCCAAGCCACACCACCCGACAGGUUCUUCUGUGACACCGAGAGAUCUAACCCAAGGCCUGGGUUAUGUCUUAGUCGAGACAUCAUCAUCUGAGAAGCACCACAUCCUUUCAGACACAUCCUCGGACACACAUGCGGUCUUGGUGCCCCCAGGUUCAAUCCUGCGUUAGCUCUUUUGAUGAGAAGGAAAUAAACCAAACCAGCCACUUGCACUAUGGCUUCCAAGCCAAUGUUAUUGACUCAAUAAGUGCUUAGCAAUUGGCUUCCUCUUUUGUCUUCCUAUUUUCAGCUCCAUUUAAACCAGGAGUUAUUUAUAAAGACCUCUUCCUCUCAUGUCUCUGAAUCCUGCAGAAUCCUGCUGUAUCGUGUUCCUCAGUCGGAACCAUAGGCUCUGGGCUGGAAAGCACUGACAUGUCAGGUGGUGAGCUUAGCAGAGAGAAACGAGUUGUGGCCUCCGACACCAGCAUCACUGAGGCUUCCGCUGUGAAGGCGGGACUUCUCACAGCAGACCCCAGGGCCUGGGCUUGGGGCAGUCAGCUGGGCUUAGGCAGAGAGGGGUUCACAUAUCAUUUCACAUCUGAAAUUAAUUCCCUUUGCUUCUCCCUGUGGUGUUUCCACCAUAAAUGGGAUGGUGUCUAAGAGACACUGUUGGUGAACUAACUGCCUUAGAACUUAGCUUUGUGGAAUCAUAGGAUGUUAGUGCUGGGAGGAGGACUUCAGCCUACCUGCCUGGCAACCUGUCUCCCUCCCUCCUUCCUUUCUCCCUGCCUCCUCCCCUUUCUCCUUCCCUCCCUUCCUCUUUUCUUCCUCCCCUUAAACAUUUCUGGAAAGCCUAUUCUGCUUUGGUCUGUGGUUGGACUUAGGAAGACAUAAGGAUAAACAAAGGCAUUAUCUGUGUCUUCUGGGGGUGCAGGGCCCAGAGAUUAUAGACCCAGUCCCACGUGCUGGGUGCUCUGGGAGGGUUAGGAGCUGUAAGAGUCUAUCAGGGAGUGGGAUCUGCUAUCCAAUCACCUCAUUUGACAGGCCCCCCGGCUGAGCCAGUCAGGGACGUGGAGAGUGCAGGCUUUAUCCCAGGCCUCCAGGCUCCUGAUCCAGGGCUCCGUUCUUGGCCAAACUUUUGUGUCUUGGCUUGGGCUUCCUGUGGGGGGGUUGUUGUGGAACCUGUGCCCUGUGCACAACACUGUUCUCAGUGCUGACUCUCACCUGCAUUCUGAGCUCUGGUCCUGGUUGGGAAAACCUCAGGUGGCUCUGAGUCUCAGUCUGCUGGUCAGGAAUGUAGGGGAGUAGCCAAGGGGAUGAAAUGAUCCCAAACACCUGCUAAACCAGGAAGAACUGCAAAGGACAGUGGAUGGUUAUUACUUGCUUGAGCUCUGCCUAUUUCUCCCAGGGAGGGAAUUUCUGGGAAAGAUUCCAGUUACCUGAGAUUUCUAGCCACUGCAUGGUUAAUUGAACCCAGUUCUUGAAACCAUGGAAUAUAAAAACUAGAAGGUUCUUAAAGACCAUUUUGUUCCACUUUAGGAAACAGGCCCAGAGCAAAGAUGUGACUGGGUCAAGUCAUGCCUGGGGCUCUACUGAGUGCCUGCUGUGGACAGAGCCCUCUACUGGAAGCCCUCUGGGUACUAGUUAUGUUCCAGAUGGGCAGUGUUUGGGGGAGGCUCCCUGGUGACACAGACAUCAGGAUUCCCACAGCUGAGGGUGUUGCAGGUUGGAAUCUGCCCCAGCCAGGGCCCUCGUAGGAGCUGAGGAUUGGAGCAUCGGGAUCCAGCCCACAGAGGAGUUGGGACACCUGGCUGCUGGCCAUAUUCCUGCCUGUGGGUCUUAGGGCCAGUCCUUCCUCUCCCUCAAUGUCUCAGUUUCCUCAUCUCUACAACUAGAAGCUUUGUAAAAAUCUUCAGCGUCUGUACAAUGUCCUUAUUUUGGGGGGACAUUCAUGAUGAAUGGAUCUAAACCAUAAUUAAUAUUUCUCAUUAUACUAGCUAGCAUUUAUCAAGCUACGUUAAGCACUUUCCCUAUAUUAUCUCCUGUAAUCAUCAUGAGACCCCUUUGGGUAAGGAGGCUCCCAUUGUACAGAUGAGGAGACAGAGGCUUAAAGCAAUUCCAGGACUUGCCCUUGGUCAGGCACCCAAUGGAGGGAACGGCACCCAAUGGAGGGAACUGCACCCAGAUCUGUAGAGCCCCAAAGUCUGUGCUCCAAACCUCUGUCUUAGCUUCCCAGACAGUGACACCAGAACAUGAGGGAUCCUGACCAAGAUGCCCCUGCAGGAUAGUACGGGGCCCUCCUCCAGGGACAAAUGCUCUAGGAGGCUGUCAUCGUCCGGGAAGCAGCCUGUGCUUAUAGGUGCCUCUCCCUAACCCUGCCGCCUACAGCAGUAGCGACUUACCCACAGUGGCACUGGAGGGGAACUGAGGCCAUCGUCACAUUUUUAAGGUGAGGAAAGAUGCCCAGAGAUAGCACAUGUUAAGUGACAACACGAAUGACUUGCCCAGGGCUACAUGGCCAGCUUGUGGCUCAACUGGGACUCACCAGUCUCCUGACUUUCAGGAUAUAGUUUUUCUGCUGCAGCCAGUGUUUAUAAGAAAAACAUUUUUUCAAAGGCUCAGAGAGACCUGGUGUUGACUCUGGAAGCCUUCUGCCAUGUUCCUCCACAGCCCUGUCACCACGCCACCAUGCAGUGCAGACUACCCAUUGAAUUAUUAUUCAAGGGAAAUCGAUUCCCGUAAACAAAACAACCAUCAUGUCUUCCUUUGUGCUAAACCCACUGCUCCAGGCUUGAAAGGCAGCAAAAACAAGUAAAUGACUCAGUGCUUAGCCAAGCACAAAGAAAGGUGGCUCAAGGUCAGAGGCAGCGUCUGAGACCAUUUCAGCAAUGCUGCUGCGGCAGCUCUGCCCACUAAUCACCUGGUGCCCAGAGACAGCAUGUGCUCAUCGCCCUUGACUUUGCUGAGAGCAGGGAGGAAGCAGAGCAGUGCUUAGAAACAACUGAGGCAGAGUAGAGUGCUGGCCAAUUUAGUGAGUGAAUUGGUGAAUAAAUUAUAUUUAUUGAGUGCUCAUGUUGUGCCAGGCAUGGUGCCAGGUGCCGGGGAGCUAGUGAUGAACAAAACGUCGUCCCUGCCCUCCGGGAGUUUGUGGUCUGGUGUGUGUGUAUACAGACGUUAAAUGACGAAUCCCACAAACGUACGUGGGAGCUGGUUGUGCUGAACACUAUCAAAUCCAGUCUCAGGGACAGUUAUCUGGGAGAGGUGGAGGAGGGGAUGACCAAAGUCAAUUCCGAAUUCUGAAGGUUGGCAGCAUAAAAAGUGUAAUGAGCAAAGCAGCAGAUACUUCUCAGAUAUCAUCCUUGACAUCCGUGUAACAUUUGACAAGGUUGGCCUCUCUGGUCUUUUUUGUUUGUUUGUUUGAGACAGAGUCUCCCUCUGUCACCCAGGCUAGAGGGUGGUGAUAUAAAUAUGGCUCACUGCAGCCUCGACACCUGGGUUCAAGUGAUCCUCCCACCUCAGCUUCCCAAGUAGCUAGGACCACAGGCACGUGCCAUUGCUCCCAGCUAAUUUGAAAAUUUUUUUUUUUUUGUAGAAACGGGGUUUUGCUAUGUUGACGAGGCUAGUCUCGAACUCCUGAGCUCAAGCAAUCCUCCUGCCUUGGCCUCCCAAAGUGCUGGGAUUACAGGUGUGAGCCACUAUGCACAGUCUCUCUGGUCUUUCUAAAGUCCUCUCCUCUUCUGUUUUCUAACUAUUCUUCCCUGACUUUCCUCCUGUCUCUCUGAAUGCUCCUUCUCAGGUUCCUUUGUGGAUUCAUCUUCCGUGAAGCUUCCUCAGGGUUCUCUUCUCUUCCUAGGAGCAUUCCUGCAGAAAUCUCAUCUAUUCAAAGCCUUAAGUAUCUUCUGCCCUGGCAUCUUAACCCCUCUACCUGCAGGCCAGUCCUCCCUAGGAGCAUUGGAAGCAUGCUCACUGUGGCCUCCUGCAUGUCUGUGUCUGCACAGCAUCUCAGACCUCAACAUGUCCUCAACUGGUAUAGUUAAAAGAACAAUCUGAACUCAGAGUCUCCUCCUACUACUUCGUAGCUGUGUGAAAUUGAGGGAGCUCCAGAAGCCCCUGGAGGCUCUGGACUCAUCAUCUGAAAUGAGGACAGGAUACCAACCACAACAGCUGUUGCAAAGCUAAGUGAAAUAGUGUUGCACAAUGCCUAGCACAGUGCCCAGCACAAACUAGACACUAGCAAGCACAGGUUGCCUUGGCCCAAAACUUGGAUCACCUUUGCCUCUUCCUUCUCCUUCACUCUUUAUGUCUAUUUGUUCACUGUAUCUUGUCAAUUCCAACUCAUAAACAUCCCUUUAAGUCAUUCCCUCCCUGCAACCCCUCUGCUACUGCCCUAACCCAGACCAUCUGAUGGAUCUUUUUGCUUUCAGAGAAUAACCUUCCAAAAAUACCUUUUGUGGGGCCCAUUGCCUACCUGUAUCAUAAACUUCAGGUUCUUUACCAAGUCAUGCAGGGAAUGUCCCAAGCUGGCUUACUCACCUUCCCAGAGAUCCUCCUGCCACCUCCCUGCCCUAUCCCAUACUAUUCCAGGCACCUUUGCACACUCUGUUCAAACACCUGGAAUGGCCCUCACACUCCUAAGUUCCUCUCUCCUUCCUUUUAUCUGGCCACUUUUGCAGAAGUCAGGUAAUGGCCCCCUGCAUCCUCCCCUCUAGAGACCUGGGCUGGGCACUCUCUCCUCUGUGCUUCUGCUGCAACCAUCACCGACUCCAUUAGGACAUCCUCACAGCACACAGCAUAAGGGCCCGUGUGUCCUUGAUAGAAGGUUUGCCUUCUCCCCAAGGGAAGACACGAUAUCUAAGCUCAUUUUGUAUUGCCAGCACUGGCGGGGAAGCACAUGCCAUGGCCACUCAACACAUGUUUACUACAGUAAUGAGGUCUCUGGUUCCUGGGGGACUCCAGCAGUUCAGGAUACCCCGCUAAUAAACUGAGUAACACCUUGGGGAAAUUGUCAGCUGAGGAGAGUCCUCUAUUGAUUUUUUUACCUAGCACAUCCCAGGAAGGCAGAGACUCCUCCUGCCUGUCCAGGGGAGCUCGGGGCUCAGGAGGCUGAAAUGUCUGUCUAGUGGGGGCUUAUGGGCUUGGCUAGCCUCUUUUUGUUUUCCCUCAUUAUAAUCCUGCUCAUCUGCUUUUUGCUGGCUAGCCAAUCCUUUUUCCUCUAGUUUAAAUGAAAGAAGGGAGAGACAUUUUCUGUGUUUCUUGUUGUCUACUUCUUCCCUUCCUCAAAGCCACACAAACAUGUCAGGCUCUUACAUCACUGUGGCUGAGGUGCAGCCUGGGAAGCAAUGUAAGAGGGAUUUAUCAAUGGUGUUUAAAAAACUAGAGGAACAUGCUGAAUGCUUUGGCUGGGAAACAGGUGAGCUGAGCUUUGCAGGAUGUCUGCUCCAGAUGCGAAGGGGAAGACCAGGAGCAUGGGGUUGUUUCCUGGGGGAAAAAAGGUGCUGCUUCUCUGAGCUCAACACACGCCCUGACCUAGUCUCCUCCCUGUAACCAGAGCACCCUCUGGGAAGAGGCUAACUGUGGCUCAGGGGUCAGGUGAGGCCAGGCGAGGGGUGCACCAGUGGCCAGGGUGUGCCUUGUGCUAUUGUUUAGAGGUCUAGUCAAACGAGGCCAGUCUGUGGAGGCUGAUUCCAUCCUACGGGGCAUCCUAAUAAACCAGUGUGAUCUUCAAAGGGUAGACUGGAUAGAUCUACAGUGUGAUCUUCAAAGGGUAGACUGGAUAGACCUACAGUAUAGAUCUACAGUAUAGAUCUACAGUCUACCCUUUGAAGAUCACAUGGGUUUAUUAGGAUGCCCUGUAGGAUGGCCUUCUGAUGGCCUGCAUCAGAAUCACCUGGGUGCUUGUUAAAACUAUGGACUGAGAACCUGGGGGAGAGGUGGCGCCUGGGAAUCAGCAUGUGUGAGGCCCUAUCUGUUCCCUGAGCAUACAACUGCUUGUGGUUCAGAAGUUGCCACCAGUUGAGUGGCCAUGUAUGGCUUGAAAUUCAGACUGGAGCCUUGAGUAGGAAAAGAAUGAAAAGAAGAAUUUGGCACACAACCCAACUUCUGCCUUUUCUGUACAUACAAAUAUAAUAUAUAACCCACUAUGUACCUAGCAACAAAAGUCAAGUGCUCGGGAAUCUAACAUUUACAAAAUUGGUUUUGCUUUAACACAAACAAAGAUUUCUUUUUCAUUUGUAAUUAUGGUAAAAUACACAUAACAUAGAAUUUAUCAUCUUAACCAUUUUUAAGUGUACAGUUCAGUAAUGGUAAGUACAUUCACACUGUUGUAUAUUCUGUCUCUGGAACUCUUCUCAUCUUGCAAAAUGAAAACUUUAAACCCAUUAAAUGACAAGUCUUCACUUCCCCCUUCCCCAGCCCCUGGCAAUCGCAAUUCUACUUUCUUUCUCUAUGAAUUUUACUGCUCUAGGUCCCUCAUAUAAGUAGAAUCAUAUAAUAUUUGUCUUUCUGAUGACUGGCUUAUUUCACUUAGUAUAGUAUACCAGAGACUUUUUAGAAUCACUUAGGUGCAAGCAGCUCUCAAAUGACAUUAACUGUUUUGGGUGUCCCUAAAGCAGAAAUCUGAUUUUUGUUUUUGUUUUUGCCUUGGGCAGUUGUCCUGGGCUGGUCGUUGGCCCCUGGCUUCCUGAGACCUUGGCCCCUUGCUGAGGGAGAGUGCAGACCUGGCCUUGCUCUGCCACCUGGGCUCCACUGUCCUGGCCAGCAUGUCCUGAGAGACAAUAGCCUUGCUGAUCUUUUAGAAGUCUUUAGGUAUUUUCCCCUGCACAGUCUCUUCUGAGAACCUUUCUUUUUUUUUUUUUUUAUUUCAAAGGAAAAAAACCAAAAGCAAAAACAUACACUUCCAUGACUUAGCUGUUGGCCACAAAAGCCAGAAAUCAGUGACUCUCUCUUCAGUUGAAGAUGGUUCCCAUGGCAACAAAUCUCUCAUUUCCUUCAACUAAAUGAUCUGCUCAGCUUUGGGGUAAAAGUUCUGUUUUCUCUAGAAUUGCCAUUUGCAACCUUGUGUGUACAUAGGAAUCACCUGGAAGUCUUUAUAAAAUAAUCCCCAAGCCAGGUCCUUUACUUCCCGGAGGAUCUGAUUCAGCAGGCCUGGGGAUAGGGCCUGGUAUCCCUAUUUUGAAAGAUCUCAUUAAGUGGUUCUGUCUCACAUGGUUGGGAGUCAUUACCCUAAGGCAGGCAGUCUAUGCCUUGGUGCACGCUAGAGUCGUCUGAAGAGCUUUAAGAAAUACUCGUGCGACCCCACCCCUUGACAUUCUGAGUCAGGUGGUCUGAGAUGUGACCUGAAUAUUAGGAUUUCACAAAUUCUCCAGAUGUUUCUAAUGUGCAGCCAGCCUUGAGAACCACUAUUCUAGGUCAGCAGUUCUCAAACUGGAGGCUGCCUCAGAAUCUCUUGGAGAGCUCCUUGAUUAUGGGCCCCGCCCCAGAGUUAUUUGGUGAGGCCAGGGUGGAGCAUCUCUAACAAGUUCCCAGGUGAUGCCAAUGCUGGUCCAGGGACUGCACUUGGAGGCUCAUGGCUCUAGAUGAUCCUUUAAUGAGAUUGGCCCUGUUCUGCUGCCCUGUUCUUUUUCCUGGUUGGGGGUUGGUGGACCCUUCCUUCCCUCAGUCUGACUCAGGCGUGAGACUUCUUAAAGGUACCAGCUUUUCUUUUUCUGAACAUUUUAGCAUUCAGAUAAAUAUUAUGACAUAUUUUUAAAGCAAAGUAACAUAGAUUUCUUCUCCCGGGGCUAGGAGCCUCAGAGUCUGCCUGAAUUAAGAAUUUAUCUGUGCCUAAGAUUAGGAUGCAUUUAGUGAUCUGAGCUAAGGGGUUGGUGGAUCUGCAGCAAUAGGUUCAGCCUGUGCCUGGGUGAGGGUCACCUUGUGACCGGCGCUGGGUAGGAUCUGAGUACCACACACUUGGCCCUCUAGCAUGGGGAGGACCUGUCUGGUCCACCUGGGGGAAAGCCUGGUUUUCUGAUGCAGACCCAGCCCUCUGCCCACCUCCACAUCUGUGCACAAACAUGGAAGGUAGCAAUGAGGAAACACAGCACCAGGACUGCCGUGAGCCCAGGAGCUAGGGUUAGAGCCUCACUUCUUUAUGCAUUUCCUUUUCUAUCAUACUUUGGAACAGGCUUGAGCUGAAACCAGAGAGUUAGUACCUGGUUUCUGCCUCAAUCUAGUCUCCCUCCUCCAAAGAUGCCCCCACAACGUGGGCAACUUCAACCCCCAUGAGAGCUCAGAAUUCCACAUUCAGCGACAAAGUUGACAAGAGCCUCUGGAGAUCUCAAAGACUUAUUAAAAGUGGAAAUGGCUACUGUUUUACUGAGGCAGGGUGAAAACACAACUCACUUCCUAGGAUCGAACCCAGCAAAUUCACUCAGCCCCCAGGUAACUGAGGACUCAGUUGAAGGAAAAUAAUUUUGAGCCCCUGAAAAUAGAUGCUAUAAAGCUGUGUAUCAAGGGCCAACCAUUUUGCUAAUAUCACAUAUCUCACGGCAUUUGCUUUGAUUUUAAAUUCAGUUCUAGUGAACUUGGUUCUGAUUUCUAAUGACAAAGCAAACUAAGAGAAUGAUGACAUGUGCUAGAUAAAGCAAGAAGUGGCAGCUAAUAGCCUAAAUUGUGAUGGCAUUAAGAAGACCAAAACUAGUUUACUUGUUCAACGACAGCUUGUCUUUGGAAAAAAAAAAACACUACAUUAAGGAUAAGAAAAUAUGUCCAGGCAUGGUGGCUCACAUCUGUAAUCCCAGCAUUUUGGGAGGCUGAGGCGGGAGAUCGCUUGAGCUCAAGAGUUGACGACCAACCUGGGCAACAUGGCAAAACCCUGUCUCAAUAAAGAAUACAAAAGCACACCUGUAGUCAGUCCCAGCUACUCAAGAGGUUGAGGUGGGAGACUGGCUUGAGCCCAGGAGGCAGAGGUUGCAGUGAGCUGAGAUCAUACCACUACACUCCAGCCUGGGUGACAGAGCCAGACCCUGUCUCAAAAUAAUAAUUAAAAAAGACCAAAACUAAAUACAUAUCUCAGGAACCAUCAAGUAGCCUGAGGUCGUUGGUCGUUUAGUGGGGAAGAGAGGGAGAAUAUGUUAUAAUAACCCCGGGAGCAACACAGCAUUUCAGCUCAGUUCACCCUGUGACAUCCAGGACAUGCAGAGGUAAAAAAGCGUUCCAACAAUGUUCAAUACACUGUCUAAGAAGGCAGGGCUGCGUUUUAUCCACUUUAGAAUUAUUUCCAUCCCCAAACAGUUAAAAUACUUUCACAAAAGUCUUGGUGCUUAAAAGAUAAAUGCUCAGUGACCUGGAAGUUCACAUAAAUGAAACGGUUGAUGAUCUGAUGAUGAAGGAUAGGCGAGAUGGGUAAACUCACUCUUUUUUUUUUUUUGAGAUGGAGUCUCACUCUGUCACCCAGGCUGGAGUGCAGUGGCAUGAUCUCGGCUCACGGCAACCUCCGCCUCCCAGGUUCAAGUGAUUCUCCUGCCUCAGCCUCCCAAGUAGCUGGGAUUACAGGCGCCCACCACUUUGCCCAGCUAAUUUUUGGUAUUUUUAGUAGAGACGGGGCCACCAUUUUGGCCAGGCUGGUUGUGAACUCCUGACCUCGUGAUUCGCCCACCUCCUCCUCCCAAAGUGCUGGGAUUAUAGGUGUGGGCCACCGUGCCCGGCCAAACUCACUCUUUUGAACUUAACAUUUUCCCCCUGACAUUGGAGACUCUCCUGCUACCUCUCUCCUAAGAAAAAAGGGCAGGUGGUGGGGGGACAAGCCCCUUCCACCUUCCCAUCUCCAAGGGACUUUGCAGUGUGGGUGAUGGUGUGGCUGAUCAUCCUCUUUCUGCACCUCUGAUUCUGCUUGUGUUGUCCUUAUUGUGUGGGGCAGGAGGGUCAGGACUUCAGCUAGGGGUGUGCUGGCUCUGCAGUGACUCAGGCCUGGGUGUUUUUUGGUGAAUUUAAAAAGAUGACCAUUUCUGGGGGAAAGUGACACUUUUACUUUCUCCACACCUUCACCAUCCAUUUUCUUACUGGACUUCGCUGCGUUCCUGCAAGGAGGACAGGGCAGAGAGUAGCAACCCUCCUUGCCGAGGCCCAGAAAGAUAGCGUGGUGUGCCCAGGGCACCCAUGGUGGGUGAUGGACAUCUCCUUUUGGGUGCCAAGGCUUCCUCAAGGUGGGAGGAACUGGAGGGCAGGGGACGGUGGCCAGUGUCCCGCUCUAGCCCUCUAGGGCACCUUUUUCUCCCCUCUGAAGUUGUUAGGCUGAUCUGGAGUCUGCUCCAGGCCUGGGCUUCACCCUGGCCUCAUGCCCUGCCCAGCACCUGUGUGGAGGGACCUGUUCGUAUUCAUUCCUCUUUGGGGGCCAAGCUCAGGGCACCCGAACCAGCAGCCUUGGGUGGCUGAACCUAGUGGGACAGAAGGGAGGCAGUUGUAUCUGGCAGAGUCACCCAAGGCCACAGGCCUGAGCAAAGCAGGAGAGCGGGGCAAGCUGGGGUCAGGGACCAUGGUGCUGGCCCCCUGCUGCUCUGGCCAUGUGGGAGGCAGCUGGAGGGGUCCCAAGUGGCAGCUCCUGCCAGACUACCCCGGACUCCCGAGCCCAUCGUCCUGUACUCUUCUCCAGUGGGACGUCUGGCCCUCACUGUGGCUAGCUUCUGGGCAAGUCCCUCUGCUCAAGAUCACUUUAUGGGGCAGCUGGUGCCCCCUGGGGCUCCCACACUCUGCACAUACAAUUUAGGGACCUGGCAGGGUCUUGGUGGCCUGCAGCUUCCCUUUCUGGAACCGACUCGCCUCCCAUCAGAGAGCCAUAACUCUUCUUCAAUACAGUAUUGUUUGAACUUUGAAAUAUAUGCAUUUGUCUAUGUAUUUUCUUAAAAAUUAACACUGUAUCUCAAUAAGCAUACAAUGGAUUGUUCAAUGGUACAGUUUGGAACCAAUCCCCCGCCACUUCCCUCCCCAAGUAAAGCCAGGACAGAUGCUGGAGUCAGCAUGGGAGCUGUGGAAACCUUUUGCCCUGGAGCCAGGUGCCUGUGGCUGUGCCUGGGAGUGGCUUCAGCCCAGGCGUGGUGUCAGUUUCCUGGCACCCCUGCCCAGGAGCCUGCAUGAAGGCAGCCGGGUCUCUCUCUGAGUGGCUGGUGCACCGGCUCAUUUCUGAGUGGCCUCCUGCGUAUGAAGAAAAAGCGGCCACGUGGCAUGCCUCCCUUCCCUCCCUUGCUUUCCUCUCAAAGAGCCAAGUCACGCUGCACUGCGCUCCGUGGAGCCUUUCCCGAUGGAGAAGAGAAGGGAGGCCUGAGAUGUCCUUUGCUGGGAUGUGGAGAAACACCAUCUAUAUGAAAAGCCCCUUGCUUGCUCUGCUGAUUUUCUCCCUCCCCUGGCCCUGGAGAGAAAGGCUGUGCCAUUCAAAGACAGUUUGGGGACAUGGGGGCUGCAGGCCUGAUCUUAUUUUUAUGCAAAUUUUGUUCUGGGAGCAGUGGUUUAUACAAACUCCUGUAGCAUAAUUCCAGCUUGUGUGUGGCUGUCCUUGAGUAGUGAUUCUGAAGUGAUGACUGUGAUGCUAUGCCUAAAAACAUCAUCAGGGUACUUUGUAUCUGUCACUGUGUUUGAACGGCCCUCAAUUUCUAUCUAAUAAAACCAGUCAAAUGGUUCACCUA